AACCUGCCCAAGGUUGAACAUGCUUGUUUGUUUUUCUUUUGCUCUCCAAAAAUCUUUAUGCUAGCGUAAAGGCCUGUUGUAAUCACAUAAAUUACUCACUAUGUAACAGGAGAAGUUGAAAUUUGUCCCUGAAACAUAAAGAUUAUAUAUAAUAAAAGCCUUAAAAACCUACCUAUUGAGAACCAAAGAUAUUUAGUGCUGUUUCCUAACUGGCAUUACAAGAAAAUUCUGCUCAGUCAGGGGAUACUCACCUUUCAAGGGACAAGGAACAUGUAAUGAAUUUAAAUUUGGUUUAGAUCUGUGUAAUAAGGAAAAGUAAGUGAAUUUGGUGAUCUUGUACCUGAGGAUGGCGGCAUUAAAAAAAGACUAUUUUAACUUAAUAUCAUUUCAUUAACUUCUUUAAAAAUAAGCUAGUUCAGCUGAACUACACAAUAUCAGAAGACCAAGUGUAAGAAAACGGUAAUCGGCCGGGCGCGGUGGCUCACGCCUGUAAUCCCAGCACUUUGGGAGGCCGAGGCGGGCGGAUCACGAGGUCAGGAGAUCGAGACCAUCCUGGCUAACACGGUGAAACCCCGUCUCUACUAAAAAUACAAAAAUUAGCCAGGCGUGGUGGCGCGCGCCUGUAGUCCCAGCUACACGGGAGGCUGAGGCAGGAGAAUGGCGUGAACCCGGGAGGCGAAGCUUGCAGUGAGCCGAGAUCGCGCCACUGCACUCCAGCCUGGGCGACAGAGCGAGACUCCGUCUCAAAAAAAAAAAAAAAAAAAAAAAAAGAAAACGGUAAUCUGUGUUUGUGGAAACAUAGAGAUGAAUUCAUCUAGUUAUGUAUCAUUAUGUAAACAUAGUUACAUUGCCUUUUGUGAUAAAUAGGUUUUGGAAAUGAAGAUUACUUAAGAAUAUAUGUAGUCAAGACUUAUAAAAACUCAGGAAUUAAAUUGUCAAAUUAACCUCUACUUGGAAUAUUAUUUAUUAAUUACACAUUUACUGAGUGUAUUCUAGUAUAUUGAGUGUAUGUACAAGGCUCAUAUACUGGGUAUAUAAAGAAAAUGUAUUUAAGCACCUUUCCUCCCAGGAACUGGUAGUCUAGUAUUCUUACUUUUCCAAGGAAAAACAAACAAACAAACAUGAAGAAAUAUAUCUCUUUAGUAUGGAUGAUCUACUUCACAUAAAGUAAUUUUAUGCUGGACAUUUCUUUUAAAACUUUACAUUUAUUCUGUUAGAGUCUCUUAUUUAUCUUUCAAAACUCAGAUGAAAAUUCAUCAGUUAGGAAUUGUGUUUAUCUGCAAGUAAGAGGGUCUUUGAAAACAGGACGAAGUAAGAUUCGAGUAAGCUUUCCUUUCACAUCAGACCCAGUUCUGAGAGUAAACGAGCAGAUACAGGGACUCCUUGGUAUUCUGAGAGGCCUGGGCUCCUUUUCUCCGGUUGUGUUUAGCCUCGGCUUCUAUGAGACAAGUUCCCUCAAGUCUGAAUAUGGCUGCUGCAGGUCUGGACAUUACAGCCAUGUUCCAGGCAGAAAGAGGCAGGAUGGGCAUAAGGGGAAUAAAAAGGAAAACAAGAAAACUUUUUUGAAAACUUUCACAGAAGCCCCAUUCAGAAACUUCUGCUUCCAUUUAAAUCAUCAUCGUUAGUUAUGCAAUCAUCAUCAUUACAAGAGAAGGUGGGAAUUGUGGCAUUUCAGUUCCUCUCAAUGCCACCUUCAACAAAUUUAGGAUUCCGUUAGUUAAGAACAGGCAGGCAAACAGCAAUCUGUGUGACAAUACACUCUAAUCAUUUAUCACCCUCUGGGGGAGAUUAUUGUAUAGACAUUGCUAGUGCCCCACCCAUGCUCUUUUUAUAGGGCUGGUGCACCCAUCCCCAGCUGCUCUGCAUUCUGGCCGUUUAUGGCUCACAGUUGUCACUUUCUCAAAGGAAUUGCCCUCCACCAAAAGGAGCCACAUUGCUUAGAGAUGCCUGGAACAUCAACCCGCUCCAACCCCACUCCUCCCCGUACCAGGCUGCCUGCAGCCAGUGACUGUCUGAUAUGGGGUAGAAAACAGGCCCCAGGCUCCCAGGUGGGACAACUUUGUGUUGUCGUUUGGGCUCAAAGCUAUGGGAGGGGUCAGGUUGAGGCCACACUCCCAUUGCACCAACGUAUAUGCUUGCUGCCAUGCCUCACUGCCUGUCCCAGUAAAUCACUUGCUAACAAUCUCUACUCUAGGGUCUUUCUCAGGGGAAUUAAAACAAUUGUUUUUUCUUGUAAUGUCCUCAUUCCCCCAGCUUCCUCCUGAGCUACUAUGUAAGAAUUGAACAUUAUUGUACUACCUCCUUCUCUUCCAAAUACACGUUCAGACUAUCAAACCUAAUCACUGGACCAGCAAACAGAGAAGGCAAGAUAGAGAGGAAUCCAAACUGGUUUUCACUAAACAUAAAUACUAUUGUAGGUUUUUCUAAGUGAAAGUAGAGGCAAAAUUAUUUAGAGAAAAUAGUUUGCCCCAUAAAGAUACUUAUUUUCAUUUCCAUGGUCUGAAUGCUUGUUUGCUACAAGUUUGAAACAAAUUAAACACUGUGCUGUAGGCAAAGGAGAGGAAUGUGCCAGCCUAGGCUGGGCGACACUGCAAGAGAGUAGUAUUUCCUGAAAGCGUAAUUCAGGAGCCAACUACAAAUAUUUUGAAUUUCAUGAAUAUUGUUCAAUUAAUUCUAUAUGAGCACAGUUUAAAUAAGCAUUGGUGGUACUUAGUAACUAAAGUUUUUCCACAGAUGUGUUAUCAUUAUUUGAAUGACAUCUGCUUCUUUGUCUAUUUCAACAAAUAGAUCCUUGCUCCCCCUGUUUUGAGGGAUCAUCUCAGACACUAACUUCCCGAAGACAAUAGAUGUGCAUCUUCAAAUGCAGCAUCCUGUGCCAGGUGCCUUGCGCUGGGUCCAGAAUGUGGAUGGUGUGUUCAAGAGGAUUUCAUUUCAGGUGGAUCAAGAAGUGAACGUUGUGAUAUUGUUUCCAAUUUAAUAAGCAAAGGCUGCUCAGUUGAUUCAAUAGAAUACCCAUCUGUGCAUGUUAUAAUACCCACUGAAAAUGAAAUUAAUACCCAGGUGACACCAGGAGAAGUGUCUAUCCAGCUGCGUCCAGGAGCCGAAGCUAAUUUUAUGCUGAAAGUUCAUCCUCUGAAGAAAUAUCCUGUGGAUCUUUAUUAUCUUGUUGAUGUCUCAGCAUCAAUGCACAAUAAUAUAGAAAAAUUAAAUUCCGUUGGAAACGAUUUAUCUAGAAAAAUGGCAUUUUUCUCCCGUGACUUUCGUCUUGGAUUUGGCUCAUACGUUGAUAAAACAGUUUCACCAUACAUUAGCAUCCACCCCGAAAGGAUUCAUAAUCAAUGCAGUGACUACAAUUUAGACUGCAUGCCUCCCCAUGGAUACAUCCAUGUGCUGUCUUUGACAGAGAACAUCACUGAGUUUGAGAAAGCAGUUCAUAGACAGAAGAUCUCUGGAAACAUAGAUACACCAGAAGGAGGUUUUGACGCCAUGCUUCAGGCAGCUGUCUGUGAAAGUCAUAUCGGAUGGCGAAAAGAGGCUAAAAGAUUGCUGCUGGUGAUGACAGAUCAGACGUCUCAUCUCGCUCUUGAUAGCAAAUUGGCAGGCAUAGUGGUGCCCAAUGACGGAAACUGUCAUCUGAAAAACAACGUCUAUGUCAAAUCGACAACCAUGGAACACCCCUCACUAGGCCAACUUUCAGAGAAAUUAAUAGACAACAACAUUAAUGUCAUCUUUGCAGUUCAAGGAAAACAAUUUCAUUGGUAUAAGGAUCUUCUACCCCUCUUGCCAGGCACCAUUGCUGGUGAAAUAGAAUCAAAGGCUGCAAACCUCAAUAAUUUGGUAGUGGAAGCCUAUCAGAAGCUCAUUUCAGAAGUGAAAGUUCAGGUGGAAAACCAGGUACAAGGCAUCUAUUUUAACAUUACCGCCAUCUGUCCAGAUGGGUCCAGAAAGCCAGGCAUGGAAGGAUGCAGAAACGUGACGAGCAAUGAUGAAGUUCUUUUCAAUGUAACAGUUACAAUGAAAAAAUGUGAUGUCACAGGAGGAAAAAACUAUGCAAUAAUCAAACCUAUUGGUUUUAAUGAAACCGCUAAAAUUCAUAUACACAGAAACUGCAGCUGUCAGUGUGAGGACAACAGAGGACCUAAAGGAAAGUGUGUAGAUGAAACUUUUCUAGAUUCCAAGUGUUUCCAGUGUGAUGAGAAUAAAUGUCAUUUUGAUGAAGAUCAGUUUUCUUCUGAGAGUUGCAAGUCACACAAGGAUCAGCCUGUUUGCAGUGGUCGAGGAGUUUGUGUUUGUGGGAAAUGUUCAUGUCACAAAAUUAAGCUUGGAAAAGUGUAUGGAAAAUACUGUGAAAAGGAUGACUUUUCUUGUCCAUAUCACCAUGGAAAUCUGUGUGCUGGGCAUGGAGAGUGUGAAGCAGGCAGAUGCCAAUGCUUCAGUGGCUGGGAAGGUGAUCGAUGCCAGUGCCCUUCAGCAGCAGCCCAGCACUGUGUCAAUUCAAAGGGCCAAGUGUGCAGUGGAAGAGGCACGUGUGUGUGUGGAAGGUGUGAGUGCACCGAUCCCAGGAGCAUCGGCCGCUUCUGUGAACACUGCCCCACCUGUUAUACAGCCUGCAAGGAAAACUGGAAUUGUAUGCAAUGCCUUCACCCUCACAAUUUGUCUCAGGCUAUACUUGAUCAGUGCAAAACCUCAUGUGCUCUCAUGGAACAACAGCAUUAUGUCGACCAAACUUCAGAAUGUUUCUCCAGCCCAAGCUACUUGAGAAUAUUUUUCAUCAUUUUCAUAGUUACAUUCUUGAUUGGGUUGCUUAAAGUCCUGAUCAUUAGACAGGUGAUACUACAAUGGAAUAGUAAUAAAAUUAAGUCCUCAUCAGAUUACAGAGUGUCAGCCUCAAAAAAGGAUAAGUUGAUUCUGCAAAGUGUUUGCACAAGAGCAGUCACCUACCGACGUGAGAAGCCUGAAGAAAUAAAAAUGGAUAUCAGCAAAUUAAAUGCUCAUGAAACUUUCAGGUGCAACUUCUAAAAAAAGAUUUUUAAACACUUAAUGGGAAACUGGAAUUGUUAAUAAUUGCUCCUAAAGAUUAUAAUUUUAAAAGUCACAGGAGGAGACAAAUUGCUCACGGUCAUGCCAGUUGCUGGUUGUACACUCGAACGAAGACUGACAAGUAUCCUCAUCAUGAUGUGACUCACAUAGCUGCUGACUUUUUCAGAGAAAAAUGUGUCUUACUACUGUUUGAGACUAGUGUCGUUGUAGCACUUUACUGUAAUAUAUAACUUAUUUAGAUCAGCAUAGAAUGUAGAUCCUCUGAAGAGCACUGAUUACACUUUACAGGUACCUGUUAUCCCUACGCUUCCCAGAGAGAACAAUGCUGUGAGAGAGUUUAGCAUUGUGUCACUACAAGGGUACAGUAAUCCCUGCACUGGACAUGUGAGGAAAAAAAUAAUCUGGCAAGUAUAUUCUAAGGUUGCCAAACACUUCAACAGUUGGUGGUUGAAUAGACAAGAACAGCUAGAUGAAUAAAUGAUUCGUGUUUCACUCUUUCAAGAGGUGAACAGAUACAACCUUAAUCUUAAAAGAUUAUUGCUUUUUAAAGUGUGUAGUUUUAUGCAUGUGUGUUUAUGGUUUGCUUAUUUUUGCAAGAUGGAUACUAAUUCCAGCAUUCUCUCCUCUUUGCCUUUAUGUUUUGUUUUCUUUUUUACAGGAUAAGUUUAUGUAUGUCACAGAUGACUGGAUUAAUUAAGUGCUAAGUUACUACUGCCAUAAAAAACUAAUAAUACAAUGUCACUUUAUCAGAAUACUAGUUUUAAAAGCUGAAUGUUAAUAGGGGACACUGUAAAGUAUCAUCAAAACCUGAAUAGCUUCAUUGUGCACAAGUGUGGAGUUUUGUAUCCUCUUACCUGGUAAACUGAAGGGAUUGUUUGGCCAUUUCAUUUAUCUUAUCAUUAAUUCACAAGAUAGUUAGAAAUUCUGCCUCAAGCAAAGUACCACAUUUUGAAUGUUUUCUUAGAUUUUGAUUGCAAGUAGAUAUCAGCAUUUUUUAAAUGAAAAGCUAUAUUAUCUUCUCCCUUCAAGGCAGCCUAAGGAUGUUCUUUCCCAGAAUCACUCCAACCCUUCUUGCCAGAAUUCAUAAAAGUACAAAAUUGGAGAAUAGAUGAUAUCUUAGAAAUAAGCUUUUUUUUUUUUUUUUUUUUUUUUUGAGACGGAGUUUCACUCUUGUCACCCAGGCUGAAGUGCAAUGGCGCAAUUAGGGUUCACUGCAACCUCUGCCUCCCGGGUUCAAGCAGUUCUCCUGCCUCAGCCUCCUGAGUAGCUGGGAUUACAGGCAUCCACCACCGUGCCCAGCUAAUUUUUGUAUUUUUAGUAGAGACGGGGUUUUGCCAUGUUGGACAGGUUGAUCUCAAACUCCUGACCUCAGGUGAUCUACCCUCCUCGGCCUCCCAGAGUGUUGGGAUUACAGGCAUGAGCCACCAUGCCAGGCUGCUAAUUCUCCUUUUUAGUGAGUUAGGGAACUGAGCCUCAGAAAACUUAAACGAUUUCUCAGAAAACACUCAAGUGAUAAAGUGGCCACAUUGGAAAGGAGUUUUUAUCUUCUCAUUGUCAGGCCAGUGUUCAUUGCACAAUAUCAUGCUACCUCUUGAAUCUUUAAAAUAUUCAAUUGGCAAAUGUUUUUCAAUGUGAUUUACUCAUGUCUUAAGUGUAUGAGGAAAGUUCAAAGCAAAAUAGAAAGGAAUAAUUCAAACUGAAUUGUCCAUAAUCAGCUUCCAGUCUUUCAUGCUAAUCAGCUUCUUAAGAGACUGAAGUAUGGCAUACCUACAGGGGAAUUCCUUCGCACCAUAGCCUGUAUGAACAGUGUUCCCUGGAGUUCUCCAGUGCUCAGCUUGAGACCUUGAUACACGGGCCAUGAGCCCUGUCUUCCCCAAUGGAAAUUUAUUUACACUUACCUUAUCCCUAUGGACUUAGUCUGAUUUUAUUGGCUAGGAGUCUAACAGUCCUGUGUGGAUAUACAGUUUUGCCCAUGACAACAAAGGAAUCUAUCCGAAAUAUCUUUUUUUUUAUAAUAAACUUCCAAGAUUUGCUGUCUUCCAGCACUUGAGUUAAAGUACUAGAUACUGCAUUUUGAUGAAGACUAACCCCAUCUCAUAUUCUACCCUAAAGAGAACUGAAAAACCUAUAAUAAGUUGUUCUGGAGCCAAUAAACACAGCAGCUCUGUUAGAUGUCCUCUACAGCCAAGCACUUUCAAUGCUAACUUGAACUGCAUUUCCUUCCUCAAAUGAGAGAUUGACAUAAUUCAGUACUGUGAGUCACUUGUAUAAGAAACCUUUGAUCACUAAAAAUAAUGUAAAAAUUGGGUUUAGUAGCCUAAUACACAUAACGUUCUUCUUAAAAAGGAAAAUGGAUGGAUGCCUGACAACCCUCCAAAAGAAAAAAGUGUAAGAUAGCCAUUAAGAUGAUGACAAUUUUUGAAAUGAACAUUAUGAUAUUUAUGAACAAUAAACAAAUUUCCGUAUGGAAUGAAUUAUCCAAAAAGAGUAUAACAAAAUGAAAUCCUUAAAAAUCCAGAGUUUAUAUUUUUUUUAUACCCUCACUUGUUUGCACUAACUUUAUAGUGGACCAAGGCUGUUACCAUAGGAAGGGACAAACUUCCUUGUAGGCAACUCAGUGUUAGACGAUGAUUGUGGUUAUGCUUGCAAAGUCUUGUGCUUAUCUUUUUUGUUUUUACUUAAAAAGCUAAUUUUUAAAGAUUGUAGGGCUUGUAUUUUACUUGAAUAAUUGAUAUCUUCCUGUGUAAUGAUUUGUGAGAUGAGAAUUAAUAUUUGACUAGUUAGAAUUAAUUAAAUGGUAAGGGAACACAGGGUACUCUUAGGUUAAAUAAUGUAUGCAAAUAGAGUCUAUUUUCAACUAAUAUGGCCACAGGAGCCUUUUGAGAUUCAUUGAUAUUAAACACAAUUAAUGAAAUUUUAAAUUGUUAACAGAAUUGAGAACUUGAACAACACUUUUAGUACUGCAGCAUUUUUGUGCCCUAAAGUAUGUAAUGAUUUAUAAAUGUGCCAUACAUACACUACAACAUAACAUUUGCUUUGUUAUGCAUUUUAUUUCUCUGGGGACACCAUUGCACUGCAGUGCACACGUAUUUAUAAACAUUUGUUAUAUUUUUGGAAACUUGCUAAUAUUUAUUAAGUCAUAGACUUUUCUGGAGGACUUAAAAAUUCACUAAAAAUCUGAUUAUGUCUUAAAUGUUCAGUUUAUCUUUGGUUUAUUAAAAUAAAAAAAAAAUCUAAGAUUAAACACAGUAGAUAUCUCUGGAGGCAAUUUUCCAAAACUCAACAUUAAAAUUUGUGGAUGCAUGAGAUGCAAUCCUUCAAAGAAUGAAUCUGAAAUAUAUUUUUAAUAUUUACUUAAUAUCCACUGAAGAUAUCUUUAUGCAAGACAAGAGUCAGCCAUCAGACACUGAAAUAUAUUAUGAUAGAUUAUGAAGAAUUUUCUCUGUAGAAUUAUAUUCUUCCUGGAACCUGGUAGAGUAGAUUAGACUCAAAGGCUUUUUCUUCCUUUUCUUACUCCUGUUUUUUCCACUCACUCUUCCCAAGAGAUUUCCUAAAGCUUCAAGCUUAAUAAGCCUAAUAGUGAAAAAUAACUGAAUUUAAUGGUAUAAUGAAGUUCUUCAUUUCCAGACAUCUUUAAUUGAUCUUAAAGCUCAUUUGAGUCUUUGCCCCUGAACAAAGACAGACCCAUUAAAAUCUAAGAAUUCUAAAUUUUCACAACUGUUUGAGCUUCUUUUCAUUUUGAAGGAUUUGGAAUAUAUAUGUUUUCAUAAAAGUAUCAAGUGAAAUAUAGUUACAUGGGAGCUCAAUCAUGUGCAGAUUGCAUUCUGUUAUGUUGACUCAAUAUUUAAUUUACAACUAUCCUUAUUUAUAUUGACCUCAAGAACUCCAUUUUAUGCAAUGCAGACCACUGAGAUAUAGCUAACAUUCUUUCAAAUAAUUUUCCUUUUCUUUUAUAAUUCCUCUAUAGCAAAUUUUUAUGUAUAACUGAUUAUACAUAUCCAUAUUUAUAUUUCAUUGAUUCCAAGACAUCACUUUUUCAAUUUAACAUCUCUGAAAUUGUGACAUUUCUUGCAACUGUUGGCACUUCAGAUGCAGUGUUUAAAAUUAUGCUUGAAUAAAUAUUACACUAAUCCAACUUUACCUAAAUGUUUAUGCAUCUAGGCAAAUUUUGUUUUCUUAUAAAGAUUUGAGAGCCCAUUUAUGACAAAAUAUGAAGGCGAAAUUUAAGGACAACUGAGUCACGCACAACUCAACAUGGAGCCUAACUGAUUAUCAGCUCAGAUCCCGCAUAUCUUGAGUUUACAAAAGCUCUUUCAGGUCCCCAUUUAUACUUUACGUGAGUGCGAAUGAUUUCAGCAAACCCUAACUUAACUAACAAGAAUGGGUAGGUAUGUCUACGUUUCAUUAACAAAUUUUUAUUAUUUUUAUUCUAUUAUAUGAGAUCCUUUUAUAUUAUCAUCUCACUUUUAAACAAAAUUAACUGGAAAAAUAUUACAUGGAACUGUCAUAGUUAGGUUUUGCAGCAUCUUACAUGUCUUGUAUCAAUGGCAGGAGAAAAAUAUGAUAAAAACAAUCAGUGCUGUGAAAAACAACUUUCUUCUAGAGUCCUCUUACUUUUUAUUCUUCUUUAUCAUUUGUGGGUUUUUCCCCCUUGGCUCUGAUCACUUUAACUUCAAGCUUAUGUAACGACUGUUAUAAAACUGCAUAUUUAAAUUAUUUGAAUUAUAUGAAAUAAUUGUUCAGCUAUCUGGGCAGCUGUUAAUGUAAACCUGAGAGUAAUAACACUACUCUUUUAUCUACCUGGAAUACUUUUCUGCAUAAAAUUUAUCUUUGUAAGCUAACUCUAUUAAUCAGGUUUCUUCUAGCCUCUGCAACCUACUUCAGUUAGAAUUGUCUAAUACUGCUCUAUUAAUCAGGUUUCUAGCCUCUACAACCUACUUCAGUUAAAAUUGUCUAAUACAGCAAUAUUUAAAAAAAAAACACUGCAAUUGUCAAGGAUGGAAAAUGUGUGAUUUGUGUAAACAAUUUUUACCAACUUUACAUUUUCCUACAGAUAAAUGUGAAAUUUUGAUAAGAAGUCUACGCAAUGACAAGUAUGGUACAUAAAUUUUAUUAAGAAUAUUGAGUAUAAAGUACUUUAAUUCUAAAUUAUAAGAAAAUAUACAUUUGCACAUAUUAAUAUAGAAAUUCAUUUUGUGUAUAUUUAACAUAGCUUUUAAACUAUUUUACAUUAGCUACUUCAUUAUGGUUUCUUGAACUUCUGAAAAAAAUUAGAAAUGUAUUAAACUUAUCAGUAACAUAAAAACUUAUUUUGUUUCACCUAACGAAUACUGCGUUUGUAAAAAUAAAUUUAAUAUAGAAUAUAUUUUUAAAUUAAAUAUUUGAAUAUAAAAUAGCUCUAAGAAAGAAGCAAAUUAUCACUGAACAUAUUUCUUAUUAUUUCUGGCUUUGAAUUAUACGUAACUUAAAUUGUCUUAAAUGAUACAGAAUAUUGGAGAAUAUGAUACUUUCACAUAAUAUACUAUGAACCUGUUCAUAUAACUCUGAUUGACUACUAACUUCUGUUUUAUGUAUUUAUUAAAGAGCUGACACUGUAGUUUGUGGUGAGAUGUUUAUUUUUCUAACAGAGCUUAUAACAGUUAGGACAAGGCAUUUAAUUAAUGCAUCAUUCUGUUUAGUAGUAGGUGUUAAUCAAUAUGAAAUUCUCUGUUUUAAAAUAAAAAUGUAAAAAUCUAA